CUUUCCUGCCUCUGAUUCCGGGCUGUCAUGGCGACCCCCAACAAUCUGACCCCCACCAACUGCAGCUGGUGGCCCAUCUCCGCGCUGGAGAGCGAUGCGGCCAAGCCAGCGGAGGCCCCCGACGCUCCCGAGGCGGCCAGCCCCGCCCAUUGGCCCAGGGAGAGCCUGGUUCUGUACCACUGGACCCAGUCCUUCAGCUCGCAGAAGGUGCGGCUGGUGAUCGCCGAGAAGGGCCUGGUGUGCGAGGAGCGGGACGUGAGCCUGCCACAGAGCGAGCACAAGGAGCCCUGGUUCAUGCGGCUCAACCUGGGCGAGGAGGUGCCCGUCAUCAUCCACCGCGACAACAUCAUCAGUGACUAUGACCAGAUCAUUGACUAUGUGGAGCGCACCUUCACAGGAGGUGGCCGGGGCAGGUGCCCCUCUGGCUUCCCUGCCCAGCCCCUGGCGGUGCCCACAGAGCACGUGGUGGCCCUGAUGCCCGAGGUGGGCAGCCUGCAGCACGCACGGGUGCUGCAGUACCGGGAGCUGCUGGACGCACUGCCCAUGGAUGCCUACACGCAUGGCUGCAUCCUGCAUCCCGAGCUCACCACCGACUCCAUGAUCCCCAAGUACGCCACGGCCGAGAUCCGCAGACAUUUAGCCAAUGCCACCACGGACCUCAUGAAACUGGACCAUGAAGAGGAGCCCCAGCUCUCCGAGCCCUACCUUUCUAAACAAAAGAAGCUCAUGGCCAAGAUCUUGGAGCAUGAUGAUGUGAGCUACCUGAAGAAGAUCCUCGGGGAACUGGCCAUGGUGCUGGACCAGAUUGAGGCGGAGCUGGAGAAGAGGAAGCUGGAGAACGAGGGGCAGAAAUGCGAGCUGUGGCUCUGUGGCUGUGCCUUCACCCUCGCUGAUGUCCUCCUGGGAGCCACCCUGCACCGCCUCAAGUUCCUGGGACUGUCCAAGAAAUACUGGGAAGAUGGCAGCCGGCCCAACCUGCAGUCCUUCUUUGAGAGGGUCCAGAGACGCUUUGCCUUCCGGAAAGUCCUGGGUGACAUCCACACCACCCUGCUGUCGGCCGUCAUCCCCAAUGCUUUCCGGCUGGUCAAGAGGAAACCCCCAUCCUUCUUCGGGGCGUCCUUCCUCAUGGGCUCCCUGGGUGGGAUGGGCUACUUUGCCUACUGGUACCUCAAGAAAAAAUACAUCUAGGGCCAGGCCUGGGGCUUGGUGUCUGACUGUCGGUGUCUCUGUGCUGUGUGAUUCCCCGUGAGCUCUCAGUAACUCACUGUCUCAUGAACACUUGGACAGCCCUCCCCGCCCUUCGUUCUGAGUAAUAAUACCGUCAGUGUGAAAACAUUCCGUAGUUUAGAAGUAGACGUUGCCAAUGCUGUGACUCAAGGCCACGGCUCUACUAAAAGAGAGAGAGGAAGCGAGAGAGAGAGAGAAAAAACAAAAAACAGAAAACACGAAUGCCUUUUCUAUCGAUUCAAGGUCUCAAGAUGGAACUGUGGAGACUGGUUAGGAUCUGAGGUGAGUCCCAGGAUGUUUCGUCCACCAGGGCCCAGAUUCUGGGAGGUGCUGGGGACUCAGAGGGCCUGACCCCUCACCUCCCCUUCCCUCUUGCCCAGGGAACUCUUCCACAGGACAAAGCCGACAUCAAGACUCAACUCCUCUAACCGGUACCUCUGAAUGGGGCUGGAUAACCGGAGACCCCAUGGGAGGUCCCUGAAGAUCAGAAGGGGCUUCACGCUUCUCCUGGACAUGGACUAGCUUGAGCCAAGGCAGUGGCACCCAAAAACCAGGCUGCAGUGGGGACGGAUACCAUGAGCACACCCUCUCAUUGUCCUUCUGAUUUGGUCCAUGUGUUGGGUUUGGCCUUAGUAGAAAUCUCUGAAGGCAGCAGCCAUCAUCCUCUUCCUACCUUGAGUUUUUCUACCCUGUGAGGUGGGACUUUCAGUAAAAGCCAUGUUGACCCUCUCUCAGAAGGUCAGUCCAGCCCAAGUGCAGGGGCGGAUCUGGAGGUGGACAAACCUAGGUCCCCCUCCUAGCCUCUGUCCAAGCCAUCUCCUUCAAUAUCCCCCCCUUCCUGUCACUCCCGGGGCUGUCCCUGUACUACACGGUGCCAUGGAGCCGGGGAGAGCGGGGAAGUCUCUGCAUCCAUGCCACCCACCCCAGUCGGGUCUCACUUUCCUGUGCCUUUUGCAUGUUGGGAAAGGGUCUUGGUGUCACUGCCGCUCAUGCAUAGAAACCACCAAAAGCCCCAAUAAAGCAUCCAGGAGGAACAGUUGCUUUUCAUUUCUAAACCUGUGCUGUCCAUCUAGUUCUCAUUGCCAAGUGCUGGAGCCAGAAGGGUAGAGAUGUGAGGUUUCAGUCUCAGUUCUUCACAAGAGCAAGCAAGAGUUGACUGCCUGUCUCAAGUUGCUGGGUCUGGGGCUGGCUUCCAGACUGACUUUCCAGGGCUCUGACCUUAACAUCAACCCAGCUCAUUUAGGCUCAGCCCUUUACAGGUUACAGGGCAUGUGUACAACCCUUUGUUCUCAUUAACCUGUGCAAGGGCCAGGUGUAGUGACUCAUAUUUAUAAUCCCAGUGCUUUGGGAGGCCAAGGCGGGAGAAUUGCUCCAGGCCAGGAGUUCAAGACAAGCCUGGGCAAUAUAGCGAGACCCCAUCUCUAGAAAAUAAAAUAAAAUAAACCUAUAUAUGGACCUCAGGGGGCACCCAGGGCACAUGCCCCCCACCCCAAUUUCCCAGAGGGAAAAAUGUAUUUAAAAUGCCCAAAGAACAUUAAAUCAGGAGUAUAAUGUGUAGAAUAUAAGGCAUGGUUUUACUUAUUUUGCAAUAAAAAAAAGUAUUAAGAA